CCUUCUUUUCCUGACUGCAGCUCUUUUCAUUUUGCCAUCCUUUUCCAGCUCCAUGAUGGUUCUGCAGGUUUCUGCGGCCCCCCGGACAGUGGCUCUGACGGCGUUACUGAUGGUGCUGCUCACAUCUGUGGUCCAGGGCAGGGCCACUCCAGAGAAUUACCUUUUCCAGGGACGGCAGGAAUGCUACGCGUUUAAUGGGACACAGCGCUUCCUGGAGAGAUACAUCUACAACCGGGAGGAGUUCGCGCGCUUCGACAGCGACGUGGGGGAGUUCCGGGCGGUGACGGAGCUGGGGCGGCCUGCUGCGGAGUACUGGAACAGCCAGAAGGACAUCCUGGAGGAGAAGCGGGCAGUGCCGGACAGGAUGUGCAGACACAACUACGAGCUGGGCGGGCCCAUGACCCUGCAGCGCCGAGUCCAGCCUAGGGUGAAUGUUUCCCCCUCCAAGAAGGGGCCCUUGCAGCACCACAACCUGCUUGUCUGCCACGUGACGGAUUUCUACCCAGGCAGCAUUCAAGUCCGAUGGUUCCUGAAUGGACAGGAGGAAACAGCUGGGGUCGUGUCCACCAACCUGAUCCGUAAUGGAGACUGGACCUUCCAGAUCCUGGUGAUGCUGGAAAUGACCCCCCAGCAGGGAGAUGUCUACACCUGCCAAGUGGAGCACACCAGCCUGGAUAGUCCUGUCACCGUGGAGUGGAAGGCACAGUCUGAUUCUGCCCGGAGUAAGACAUUGACGGGAGCUGGGGGCUUCGUGCUGGGGCUCAUCAUCUGUGGAGUGGGCAUCUUCAUGCACAGGAGGAGCAAGAAAGUUCAACGAGGAUCUGCAUAAACAGGGUUCCUGAGCUCACUGAAAAGACUAUUGUGCCUUAGGAAAAGCAUUUGCUGUGUUUCGUUAGCAUCUGGCUCCAGGACAGACCUUCAACUUCCAAAUUGGAUACUGCUGCCAAGAAGUUGCUCUGAAGUCAGUUUCUAUCAUUCUGCUCUUUGAUUCAAAGCACUGUUUCUCUCACUGGGCCUCCAACCAUGUUCCCUUCUUCUUAGCACCACAAAUAAUCAAAACCCAACAUGACUGUUUGUUUUCCUUUAAAAAUAUGCACCAAAUCAUCUCUCAUCACUUUUCUCUGAGGGUUUUAGUAGACAGUAGGAGUUAAUAAAGAAGUUCAUUUUGGUUUAAACAUAGGAAAGAAGAGAACCAUGAAAAUGGGGAUAUGUUAACUAUUGUAUAAUGGGGCCUGUUACACAUGACACUCUUCUGAAUUGACUGUAUUUCAGUGAGCUGCCCCCAAAUCAAGUUUAGUGCCCUCAUCCAUUUAUGUCUCAGACCACUAUUCUUAACUAUUCAAUGGUGAGCAGACUGCAAAUCUGCCUGAUAGGACCCAUAUUCCCACAGCACUAAUUCAACAUAUACCUUACUGAGAGCAUGUUUUAUCAUUACCAUUAAGAAGUUAAAUGAACAUCAGAAUUUAAAAUCAUAAAUAUAAUCUAAUACACUUUAACCAUUUUCUUUGUGUGCCAUCACAAAUACUCCUUAACCAAAUACGGCUUGGACUUUUGAAUGCAUCCAAUAGACGUCAUUUGUCGUCUAAGUCUGCAUUCAUCCACCAGCCUAGGCCUCCUGUCUUAAUUUUCAUACAGACAGAAAUGACUCCCCACUGGGGAAAGAGCAAAGCAAUACAUGUAGCACUCUUUUUCAAACACUGGUCUUUUUUUUUUUCUUAACAAUCCAACAUUGUUAUGUGUUUUGCGUCUCAUAUUGACACCUUUUGGUCAAGGUAGAGGACAUGUUUGUUGUAAGCUUUCUUUUUCGUGUAGAGGAUGGAUUCUUCACUCCUGAUACACACAAUCAGUGCACAGCAGCUCUCUUAUACAUCCAGUUGAUGCCUUCAGUCUCCCUGGCUUCUUACAAGCAUCUUCUGGGCCUUGUGUGUCCCUGGGCACCUGUCCCUGGUCAAUUCCCGAAAGCUACUGUGCUCCUCUUGCCCAUCUCCCCUUGCAAAUAAUAUCUUCCAUCGGGGGACCGGCUUCCUCCAAUUUCAGGAGAGGUGGGGCUGAAGGCACAGACUUGGGCGUCACUGGCACAGAUAUAAGUAAAUACAGCUGGAGUCUGCAGAGAGGCUGGACUGAGUCAGGGAGUCAGGAAAGAGAAGCCACACACAAGGACAACCAAUCAUGUUUCUCAUAAUCUUCUUAACCUAGGGAAUAGGACACAAUCAUUUUUUCUUUUUAAAACAUCUUUAUCCCUGAUCAGCCUCAUUUCCUCAAAAACUAUAAAGGAAAAUGCUGCUGACUUGUUUUUGCGUAGUAAUUUCAGCUGUCACAUAAUAAGCUAAGGAAGACAGUAUAUAGUAAAUAAGGACCCUUUAUCUGUCUUAUUUUCCCUUUUGGCUUCACAGGAAACUUGUGAGAAACCUAUGCAGCAUAAAAUUAAUAUGAUUUCAAUCCAGGGAUUCAACGAUGGAAGGAGGUCAUGAGAAUAGCAGAAAGUCUUCAAAUCGAGAUCAUUAUGAAAUCCUCAGACCCAGAGCACAUAAAUCCUACCCUCAGAGUCACUGAGCAGUUAACAUUACAAAUUACAAACCAUAUCCAGUCAGAGUCAUUCUCUUUCCUGCUUGUCUCCUGUACUCAUGUUACAGGUUAGGGCAGUACCCCGAGUGGAGUGAACAAUCUCUGGACUAACACUUGUCAGGAUCAGAAGCUGAGGUAUCUGCACCCACAUUACAGGAACAGGAUAUGUGCUCCUAGGGAACUGAGGGUGUCAGGAGAUGAGGAAUGUCCCUGGAGUCACAGAAAGAAGGUAUCAGAUGUGUCUCACUCUGACAUAUGCAGGUGUUUAUGAAACUCUGGGAUUUCUAAGGAAGGAUGCAGUGCAGAGACAGGUCCCAGAGGAGACAAGAGCUGAGAGACCAUCCAAACUGGGACCACCUUGUCACUAGACUUCAAAUUUUCAAUAUUGAUAGAGUGUUUUCUAAGAGUCAGGCCCUUUGCUGAGUGCUAUGUGCAGCAGGAUCAAAGGCAGCCAGGAGGUAGAGGAGUCUUGAGGUACAUCAGUCAUUGGAGUUGAAGAGCAGAGAUUCAAAGGAAAGUUGGAACUGGAGCUUUAAAGGAGAUGUGAAGUGGGUGACUCAACCUCUGACUCAGAAAAAUUGAUACCUGCAGAAGAAAAAACCCGGCGGGCUUAGGACUCCCAGCUGAGUGUUGUAUCCUCCAUCCCUUUCCACCUGGUCCCUUCAUUUUCUACCCCUCACAGUUCCCUAACGAGAAGGUGGUCCACCCAACAGACAACACUGCCUCAGAUGGUUAUCAAGGGGUACCCUAAGAAGAAAUCAUCUCACCCUCUCUUUGUCCCCAUUUGUCAAGUAGCAGUGAGGCCGAGCCAGGGGAUGGUGAAAGUGGAAGGAGGUGGGAGUUGGGCAUCGGGUGUGAAGAUGCUCUUGAAAGGGGUUUUAAUAACCACUUGCUACCAGGCCAGUGAACACUUACCAUAGUUGAUGCCUUUUGAGCAUGUUGCAUUGUAAACUGUCCCUGAAAUUACUGUGCACUUGGCUUAUGGGAUGAAACAUCCUCCUAGUUCUUUUGUCUCUCAGCUUCUCUGAAGUCUCAUUGAGCACCUUCUCUUCAAUUUCUUUUACACAGUAAGAAUAGGAUCAGCUGUGCUAAACUAACAAAUACCCAGAUAUCCAGGUUUGGCUCAUGUUACACGUCCAAAGUAAGUCAUGCAGGAAGCUCUGCUCAUCAUCGUACUCAGGAAGUCAGGCUGACAGUCUUUCUCCUGCACAUCUGCUCCCAGAACCUCCCCAGCAGAAUGAAGGGAACCUAAGAAUUUAUUCACUGGCUUUUAAUGAUCCCUCCUAGAAAGAACACACUUCUCGCAUUUCAUUUUCCAAUGUAAAUCAUAUGGCUGCAACUAACUUCAAAUAAGUGGGAAUACUUGAAGGUGGAAAACAUUUAAGAAGUACACACUAAAUAAAUAAUAAAAUACUUCUACAAGAGA